CGUGGUACGGAACCGGCGCCGCGCUUGCUGCUGGUAACAGGGCCUUGCCUAGUGGGCCUUCCUUCCCAGGUGGGUCUUCCUGAUGGACCUUCCUUCCCGGGUGGGCGCCCUGAGCUGGGAACGGGCUGGGCGGGGAGGACCCGGGUCAGCGGCGAGAGUCACGCCUCAUUCGUGGGGGAGCGUGGGGCGCCCGGCCGCAGCCAGGCGGGAACAAUGGUGUCCGGGCUGUUCCCGAGCGCGCGGUCGGGGGCGGAGGCCCGUGACGGCCAUGGCCCCGGGGCCUCUCGCACCUCCGGGCCACUCGUGUCCCAGCAGCGCCGAGCGCGUCCCCGGUACGCAGGGACAAGCUGGGCGGCGCACUUGGCCUGAGCCUGCGUGGCCCUCCCUGGUGGAGUCGAGUGGAACGACCCGGGUUGGAGAUGGGGUUGCGGGGAGCCGAGCGCUGGUCAGGCCACACCCCUCCCCAGGGGCCUGCUGAGAACUCCAGCCUUUCUCCAACGGAUCCCUUUCCCGGAGACCUGGGGUGGGGAGUGUGGCGGGACAGAAGCCUCCCAGGUUCAAAGGGCCCUGGACAGCGUCCCUAGCUCCCGCCAGCAUUUGAGGCAGCGUUUAAGGCUAUAGGAGGAAGCGUCUGAGGGGAGACAAAAUUCCCAUGCCAGCUUGAUGGUCUGGGGCAGGUGUCUUAUUCAAUUGGCUUCAGUUUCCUCAUCUGUGAAAUAGAGACAAUAUUUGGUCCUCACAGACAGGGCCACCAAACCAAACUCCCCACCGCCUGCCAAGGUCAGAUUCCGUAGAUCAUCCAAGCAUAGACUGCAGGAAGAGGCGGAGAACCCGGGGCCUGCUACCAAUACCUUCCUUGUCCCUAAUGUUUGCAGGCAGGAGUGGAGGAAGAGAAGUCCACAUUAUGCUUAGGGAUCAAGUUCUAGCUUGGGCAGAUUGGAGAUUCUUUUAUUGGUUCUUAAUCAGACAUGAAGGUGUGAUUCAGUUAUUUGUGUUAUAUAUGCCUUCAAUUAUCAAGGGACAGGGACUGAGAUUCUCAGAACUAGAAGACUCAUUUGUGUGUACUACUGACGGUUCCAGGUGCCACAGCAAUUUCUCCUGCCCUCCACUAGUCUCAACAUUUAAAUCAUGUUACUCCCUUGCCAGGCAUGGUGGCUCAUGUGUGUAACCUCGGCACUUUGGGAGACCAAGGCGGACAGAUCGCUUGAGUCCAGGAGUUCGAGACCAGCCUGAGUAACACGAGCAAACCCCGUCUCUACAAAAAAUACAAAAAUUAGCUGGGUGUGGUGGUGCGCACCUGCAGUCCCAGCUACUUGGGAAGCUGAGGCAGGAGGAUCAUUUGAGCCUGGGAGACAGAGGUUGCAGUGAGCCAAAAUCACAGCAAUGCACUCCUGCCUGGGUGACAGAAUGACAACCUGUCUCUAAAUAAAUAAAUAAAGUUACUCCGUAUGAACUUUAGAUUUUUAGAGGGGAGUGAGGUGUCAUUUAAAAGGAUAAUGCUUUUGCUUAAAUCAGCAUACUGCUUUUACCUUAAUUAGUGGUGUUCUCCAGAGCAUAUAAAAAUGGUUCCAUUUAAUGGCUUUGUAACGGGGGAGGUGGGGGGAAGUGAAACAGGAGUAACCCAGAAGUGUGAAUGGGAGGAGAAACUGGAACCUGGCCUAGCCUGGUUUGACUGGAUGAGUGAUUAACAGGAGUUGCUUUUUAGCCCAUCUCUGAUGGUGGAACAAUCUGAUCCCUGUUUCCUCUCUUUUAGUGAAAGUCGUAACUUAGAUAAUUACAGUCAUAUGUUGCUUAAGGAUGGGGAUACAUUCCAAGAAAAUGCAUUGUUAGGCGAUUCGUUGUUGUGUGCACAUCCUGAGCUGCGCUCACACAAACCUGGAUGGUACAGCCUCCUACAUACCUAGGCUAUAUGGUGUAGCCUAUUGCUCCUAGGCUACAAACCCGUACAUGUACCUUUACUGGAUGCUGUAGGCAGUUGUAACACAGUGAACCUUCGAGAUCUGCGGUCUGGGGUCUGGUUGAAAGAUGGCGGCCCUCACUACCCUGUUUAAGUACAUAGAUGAAAAUCAGGAUCGCUACAUUAAGAAACUCGCAAAAUGGGUGGCUAUCCAGAGUGUGUCUGCGUGGCCGGAGAAGAGAGGCGAAAUCAGGAGGAUGAUGGAAGUUGCUGCUGCAGAUGUUAAGCAGUUGGGGGGCUCUGUGGAACUGGUGGAUAUCGGAAAACAAAAGCUCCCUGAUGGCUCGGAGAUCCCGCUCCCUCCUAUUCUGCUCGGCAGGCUGGGCUCCGACCCACAGAAGAAGACCGUGUGCAUUUACGGGCACCUGGAUGUGCAGCCUGCAGCCCUGGAGGACGGCUGGGACAGCGAGCCCUUCACCCUGGUGGAGCGAGACGGCAAGCUGUAUGGGAGAGGUUCGACUGAUGAUAAGGGCCCGGUGGCCGGCUGGAUAAACGCCCUGGAAGCGUAUCAGAAAACAGGCCAGGAGAUUCCUGUCAACGUCCGAUUCUGCCUCGAAGGCAUGGAGGAGUCAGGCUCUGAGGGCCUAGACGAGCUGAUUUUUGCCCGGAAAGACACAUUCUUUAAGGAUGUGGACUAUGUCUGCAUUUCUGACAAUUACUGGCUGGGAAAGAAGAAGCCCUGCAUCACCUACGGCCUCAGGGGCAUUUGCUACUUUUUCAUCGAGGUGGAGUGCAGCAACAAAGACCUCCAUUCUGGGGUGUACGGGGGCUCGGUGCAUGAGGCCAUGACUGAUCUCAUUUUGCUGAUGGGCUCUUUGGUGGACAAGAGGGGGAACAUCCUGAUCCCCGGCAUUAACGAGGCCGUGGCCGCCGUCACGGAAGAGGAGCACAAGCUGUACGACGACAUCGACUUUGACAUAGAGGAGUUUGCCAAGGAUGUGGGGGCGCAGAUCCUCCUGCACAGCCACAAGAAAGACAUCCUCAUGCACCGAUGGCGGUACCCGUCUCUGUCCCUCCAUGGCAUCGAAGGCGCCUUCUCUGGGUCUGGGGCCAAGACCGUGAUUCCCAGGAAGGUGGUUGGCAAGUUCUCCAUCAGGCUCGUGCCGAACAUGACUCCUGAAGUCGUCGGCGAGCAGGUCACAAGCUACCUAACUAAGAAGUUUGCUGAACUACGCAGCCCCAAUGAGUUCAAGGUGUACAUGGGCCACGGUGGGAAGCCCUGGGUCUCCGACUUCAGUCACCCUCAUUACCUGGCUGGGAGAAGAGCCAUGAAGACAGUUUUUGGUGUUGAGCCAGACUUGACCAGGGAAGGCGGCAGUAUUCCCGUGACCUUGACCUUUCAGGAGGCCACGGGCAAGAACGUCAUGCUGCUGCCUGUGGGGUCAGCGGAUGACGGAGCCCACUCCCAGAAUGAAAAGCUCAACAGGUAUAACUACAUAGAGGGAACCAAGAUGCUGGCCGCGUACCUGUAUGAGGUCUCCCAGCUGAAGGACUAGGCCAAGCCCUCUGUGUGCCAUCUCCAAUGAGAAGGAAUCCUGCCCUCACCUCACCCUUUUCCAACUUGCCCAGGGAAGUGGAGGUUCCCUCUUUCCUUUCCCUCUUGUCAGGUCAUCCAUGACUUUAGAGAACAGACACAAGUGUAUCCAGCUGUCCACGGGUGGAGCUACCCGUUGGGCUUAUGAGUGACCUGGAGUGACAGCUGAGUCACCCUGGGUAAGUUCUCAGAGUGGUCAGGAUGGCUUGACCUGCAGAAGAUACCCAAGGUCCAAAAGCACAAGGUCUGCGGAAAGUUCUGGUUGUCGGCCGGGCACCACGGCUCACACCUAUAAUCGAGCACUUUGGGAGGCCAAGACAGGAGGAUCACUUGAGGCCAGGAGUCUGAGACAAGCCUAGGCAACAAAACAAGACUCUGUCUCUACAAAAAGUUUAAGAAAUGAGCCAGACAUGGUGGUGUAUGCCUGUAGUCCCAGCCACUCAGAAGGCUGAGGCAGGAGGAUCGCUUGAGACCAAGAGUUUGAGCCUGCGGUGAGCUGUGAAUGCACCACGGCACUCAAGCCUGGGCAAUGUAGCAAGAUCCUGUCUCUACAAGAAAUUUUUUAAAAAUGAGCCAAGUGUGGUGGUGCAUGCCUGUAGUUCCAGCUACUCAGGACACUGACGUAGGAGGGUUGCUUGAGACUGAGAGUUGGAGGCUGCGAUGAGCCAUGAAUGCCCCACUGCACUCCAGCCUGGGCGACAGAACGAGACCCCAUCUCAAAAAAAAUAAGUUCUGGUUGUCAUUGAAUUGGGAUAAACAGAGAGCUUGAUGCUUUCUGCCUUCUGUCUCAGGUGAUGCAUUGCACAUUUGGGAUAUUUGGAAAGGAAAUGAGGAAAGAAAUUAGGGCCUCCUCUGAUCUCUCGCUAUCUGCGGGUCCUGUCCUUUUCUCAAGACCUUCACCAUUACUGGCAUUUUCCUGUCUUCUCUUUAGUAUGAUCCCUCAAAACCUCACUAACUGGAAGGAUGAUUUUGUCUCAGUUUGUACUCCUAAAUAAAAAGUAAACAUGACACCUCUAAAAGAAUCGCUCCAUCUCAGUUGCUCGUCGCGUGCACACCAUGCUUAUUGAGUGGUGUCUGGUUGGUGGUGUCAGCUCAGGGCAGGGGACAGCAGGCAGGACCCGGAAAACAGAACCCAGGUCUUCCCAGGCGAGCACUCCCUCCCUCGUCCACACAAGUGGAGGCUCACUCGUGGCCCCCUGCAUGUUCCGAGAAGUGUCCCUGUCUCUGCUCCUUAACGGCUGUGGGGCCACAGGAAGUCCAGCUGGCUUAAACAAAGAAUUGAUUGGCCCACUUGACAUAAAAGAACAGAGUAAACUCAAUGAAAGGAAAAGGCUCCUUGAAGUGGUUGGUUCCAGGGCUGGGCAGGGAAGAUGCAAGAUGAGUCUGGACCCUCUCACAUCGGAACGUAAGGAUGCGCUCCUGAGGGCGUGGGGCUGCGUCCAAGGACACAGGAGCCAGCCUGGAAGAGUUUGCAGGGGCCCAGGGGAGCAAUUGGAGUGAGAAAAUAGCAGUAGUGUUGGAUUUUUACCAUGGAAUAAACAACAAUCCAUGAGUCCAUACUAAUAUAAAUAAAGUGACAAAGUGGGUGAGAAGGACCAGUGCCCCUGGAUGAAGAAUCUCUGCUCAUGUGGGAGGAAGGUGGGAGAUCAAAGCUGGAGCACUUGCUGCUGCAGGUGAGACCCCUGACACACUCUCAAAUUGGUAGGCAAAGGUUUAAAGAACGGGAUAUUUGCUUAGCUUAAAAGCACCUCCCAAGGGGAAAACAGUAACUUCACAGUGGAGAGACCUGGCAGGCACCACCCUCAGAUCAAAAUGAACCUCAGCAGUAAUGACACGUCCACAUCAGCACCCCCAACACCACUCCCUGAGGAGGACAUGCCAGUUCUGGGAACAUCACACUCAUCGUGACAAAACAUCAGACAAACCCAAACGGAUGAAAUGUGAGGAAAAUCUGUAGUUGGUUUUACGUGGAUGUUAAUCUCUUAGUUUUGAUCAUUGUGCUGUAGCUGCAUAAGAGGUUAGCUGGGUGAAGUGUAUCUGGGGACCCUCUAUGGCUUUUGCAUCUUUUCUCUAAGUCUCCUGUCAUUUCAAAGUAAAAACAAAAAAAGAAGACAAGGGUAGCGGCUUCAGGUACAGCUGGACCCAGCACUCAGUGCUAUCUGGGCUUGUGGCUCCAACUCAACUCCUCCAUCAGAACUGUGAGAAAUGCAUUCUUUCAGCUUCUAAUCCUGCAAAAAGAACUGCAUGGUCUUCCCCCAGAAAUCCUAAGAGUAGCUGCUGGUGUCUCAUGCAUGCGAGCUGCAUAUGGGCCCCCGUUAGUCAGGAACCCAUGCUGAGAGGUGCUAUGCUUUGAAUGUUUGGCUCCUCCCAAACUCGUGUUGAAACUUAAUAGCCAUUGUAACAGUAUUAAGAGGCAGGGCCUUCAAGAGCUGGUCAGGCCAUGAGGGCCCUGUCCUCCUGACUGAGUGAAUGCUGUUAUUGUAGGAGUGGGCUUGUUUGGCCUCCUCUUGCUCUCUCUACCCCUCUCUGAGCCCUUGUGUUGUGGGAUGACACAGCCAGAAGGCCCUUGCCAGGUUCCGGUCCCUCCACCUUGGACCUCCCAGCCUCCCGAACGUUGAGCCAAUACAUCUCUGCUCAUUGUAAAUUACCUAGUCUUGGGCAUUGUGUUACAGCAGCAAAAAGCAGCCUACGGCAGUCACCGUGCUAACACCUGCAGCAGCCUGCGGCGGUCACCGUGCUAACACGUGCAGCAGCCUGUGUGGCUCAGGCCAGUCAGCUUCCCCUGGAAGCAAGUGUGAGGUCGUCGCCUCUGGAAGUGCUAGCGGAGGGUGAUCUCCCGGAGGAAAUCAGAGUGGUGUUCUACUAGAAGGCCGAUGACUCCUGGGUAAAGUGCCAAUGCUCACCUCCAUCUCUGCAAGCUCAGUCCCUCGUGGAAUUUCCAGGAGCACAAGGGCAAUCUCGACAGCUCCACGUUCCCAGUGCCCGACCCAAGCCUGGCCCAUGAUCAGAUAAAUGCCUAAGUGGGGUGGCAUGGACAUUUGCACACGUCCAGACUGCUUUAUGUUAGAAGCUGAGCUGGCAUGCCACUAGCUGGUUUUGAUGUAAACAACAAUUUUGUAAAACCCUGGACUGAAUGGGUCUGACUAACGGCUGGUUCUGUGAACUUGAGCCUCAGCGUCCUGUGUCAGAAGAGCACAAACCACUUUCCCAGAGAGGUUAUGAAGACAGAAAUGACCCUGUGACCCCUUUGCAAAGUAUGAAGAACGGUUCCCACUCAUGCAUGGAGCUGGAUCUUCUCAAGUGGGAAACAGGCGUGGUAAAUAAAUACUGUUGUUUCAGCUGGUGUAA